AGGCCAGCUGAGUCCUGAGCAGCAGCCCAGCGCAGCCACCGAGACACCAUGAGAGCCCUCACACUCCUCGCCCUAUUGGCCCUGGCCGCACUUUGCAUCGCUGGCCAGGCAGGUGCGAAGCCCAGCGGUGCAGAGUCCAGCAAAGGUGCAGCCUUUGUGUCCAAGCAGGAGGGCAGCGAGGUAGUGAAGAGACCCAGGCGCUACCUGUAUCAAUGGCUGGGAGCCCCAGUCCCCUACCCGGAUCCCCUGGAGCCCAGGAGGGAGGUGUGUGAGCUCAAUCCGGACUGUGACGAGUUGGCUGACCACAUCGGCUUUCAGGAGGCCUAUCGGCGCUUCUACGGCCCGGUCUAGGGUGUCGCUCUGCUGGCCUGGCCGGCAACCCCAGUUCUGCUCCUCUCCAGGCACCCUUCUUUCCUCUUCCCCUUGCCCUUGCCCUGACCUCCCAGCCCUAUGGAUGUGGGGUCCCCAUCAUCCCAGCUGCUCCCAAAUAAACUCCAGAAGAGGAA